CUCGAUCCGGGCGAUGGAGGAGGAAGCAAGCGAGGGGGCUGGUUCCUGAGCUUCGCAAUUCCUGUGUCGCCUUCUGGGCUCCCAGCCUGCCGGGUCGCAUGAUCCCUCCGGCCGGAGCUGGUUUUUUUGCCAGCCACCGCGAGGCCGGCUGAGUUACCGGCAUCCCCGCAGCCACCUCCUCUCCCGACCUGUGAUACAAAAGAUCUUCCGGGGGCUGCACCUGCCUGCCUUUGCCUAAGGCGGAUUUGAAUCUCUUUCUCUCCCUUCAGAAUCUUAUCUUGGCUUUGGAUCUUAGAAGAGAAUCACUAACCAGAGACGAGACUCAGUGAGUGAGCAGGUGUUUUGGACAAUGGACUGGUUGAGCCCAUCCCUAUUAUAAAAAUGUCUCAGAGCAACCGGGAGCUGGUGGUUGACUUUCUCUCCUACAAGCUUUCCCAGAAAGGAUACAGCUGGAGUCAGUUUAGUGAUGUGGAAGAGAACAGGACUGAGGCCCCAGAAGGGACUGAAUCGGAGAUGGAGACCCCCAGUGCCAUCAAUGGCAACCCAUCCUGGCACCUGGCAGACAGCCCCGCGGUGAAUGGAGCCACUGGCCACAGCAGCAGUUUGGAUGCCCGGGAGGUGAUCCCCAUGGCAGCAGUAAAGCAAGCGCUGAGGGAGGCAGGCGACGAGUUUGAACUGCGGUACCGGCGGGCAUUCAGUGACCUGACAUCCCAGCUCCACAUCACCCCAGGGACAGCAUAUCAGAGCUUUGAACAGGUAGUGAAUGAACUCUUCCGGGAUGGGGUAAACUGGGGUCGCAUUGUGGCCUUUUUCUCCUUCGGCGGGGCACUGUGCGUGGAAAGCGUAGACAAGGAGAUGCAGGUAUUGGUGAGUCGGAUCGCAGCUUGGAUGGCCACUUACCUGAAUGACCACCUAGAGCCUUGGAUCCAGGAGAACGGCGGCUGGGAUACUUUUGUGGAACUCUAUGGGAACAAUGCAGCAGCCGAGAGCCGAAAGGGCCAGGAACGCUUCAACCGCUGGUUCCUGACGGGCAUGACUGUGGCCGGCGUGGUUCUGCUGGGCUCACUCUUCAGUCGGAAAUGACCAGACACUGACCAUCCACUCUACCCUCCCACCCCCUUCUCUGCUCCACCACAUCCUCCGUCCAGCCGCCAUUGCCACCAGGAGAACCACUACAUGCAGCCCAUGCCCACCUGCCCAUCACAGGGUUGGGCCCAGAUCUGGUCCCUUGCAGCUAGUUUUCUAGAAUUUAUCACACUUCUGUGAGACCCCCACACCUCAGUUCCCUUGGCCUCAGAAUUCACAAAAUUUCCACAAAAUCUGUCCAAAGGAGGCUGGCAGGUAUGGAAGGGUUUGUGGCUGGGGGCAGGAGGGCCCUACCUGAUUGGUGCAACCCUUACCCCUUAGCCUCCCUGAAAAUGUUUUUCUGCCAGGGAGCUUGAAAGUUUUCAGAACCUCUUCCCCAGAAAGGAGACUAGAUUGCCUUUGUUUUGAUGUUUGUGGCCUCAGAAUUGAUCAUUUUCCCCCCACUCUCCCCACACUAACCUGGGUUCCCUUUCCUUCCAUCCCUACCCCCUAAGAGCCAUUUAGGGGCCACUUUUGACUAGGGAUUCAGGCUGCUUGGGAUAAAGAUGCAAGGACCAGGACUCCCUCCUCACCUCUGGACUGGCUAGAGUCCUCACUCCCAGUCCAAAUGUCCUCCAGAAGCCUCUGGCUAGAGGCCAGCCCCACCCAGGAGGGAGGGGGCUAUAGCUACAGGAAGCACCCCAUGCCAAAGCUAGGGUGGCCCUUGCAGUUCAGCACCACCCUAGUCCCUUCCCCUCCCUGGCUCCCAUGACCAUACUGAGGGACCAACUGGGCCCAAGACAGAUGCCCCAGAGCUGUUUAUGGCCUCAGCUGCCUCACUUCCUACAAGAGCAGCCUGUGGCAUCUUUGCCUUGGGCUGCUCCUCAUGGUGGGUUCAGGGGACUCAGCCCUGAGGUGAAAGGGAGCUAUCAGGAACAGCUAUGGGAGCCCCAGGGUCUUCCCUACCUCAGGCAGGAAGGGCAGGAAGGAGAGCCUGCUGCAUGGGGUGGGGUAGGGCUGACUAGAAGGGCCAGUCCUGCCUGGCCAGGCAGAUCUGUGCCCCAUGCCUGUCCAGCCUGGGCAGCCAGGCUGCCAAGGCCAGAGUGGCCUGGCCAGGAGCUCUUCAGGCCUCCCUCUCUCUUCUGCUCCACCCUUGGCCUGUCUCAUCCCCAGGGGUCCCAGCCACCCCGGGCUCUCUGCUGUACAUAUUUGAGACUAGUUUUUAUUCCUUGUGAAGAUGAUAUACUAUUUUUGUUAAGCGUGUCUGUAUUUAUGUGUGAGGAGCUGCUGGCUUGCAGUGCGCGUGCACGUGGAGAGCUGGUGCCCGGAGAUUGGACGGCCUGAUGCUCCCUCCCCUGCCCUGGUCCAGGGAAGCUGGCCGAGGGUCCUGGCUCCUGAGGGGCAUCUGCCCCUCCCCCAACCCCCACCCCACACUUGUUCCAGCUCUUUGAAAUAGUCUGUGUGAAGGUGAAAGUGCAGUUCAGUAAUAAACUGUGUUUACUCAGUGAA